AUGGUCAACCCCACUGUGUUCUUCGACAUCAGUGUCAGUGGCAAGCCCUUGGGCCAUGUCUCCUUCAGGAUAUUUGCAGACAAGCUUUCAAAGACAGCACAAAACUUUCGUGCUCUGAGCACUGGAGAGAAAGGACUUGAUUAUAAGGGUUCCUGCUUUCACAGAAUUAUUCCAGGGUUUAUGUGUCAGGGUGGUGACUUCACGUACAAUAAUGGCACUGGUGGCAAGUCCCUCUAUGGGGAGAAAUUUGAUGAUGAGAACUUCAUCCUGAAGCGUAUACGUCCUGGCAUCUUGUCCAUGGCAAAAGCUGGACCCAACACGAAUGGCUCCCAGUUUUUCAUCUGCACUGCCAAGACUGAGUGGUUGAUUGGCAAGCAUGUGGUCUUUGGCAAGGUGAAAGAGGGCAUGAAUAUUGUGGAGGCCAUGGAGCCCUUUGGGUCCAGGAAUGGCAAGACCAGCAAGAAGAUCACCAUUGCUGAUUGUGGACAACUCUGGAUUCUGGCUGACCCCUCCAUCGAUGACCUGCUUCUGCUGGCUGUGUCCAGGGUGGCCUCCCUGAAGCCACCGGAGCAGAGGCCUGGUAUCUUCUCAGAGCAGCAGCCAACCAGGCAGCUGGAGGAAACCCCUGGUCUCUUUUGCAGCCAAAGUGCCAGGCCUGUGGCAAAGCAGGUAACCUUUGAAACGGAAUCUGAUCUGCUGUCGGCCACUGCCCAGGCCACAGUCUGCCAAAGGGACAGCUGA